AGCGAGAGGCUCUGAGGCUGCCAGAGUGGUUGUGUCUGUUCCUCCGGUAAGGGGUGAUUCGCCGAGGGGCGCGGACCAGACAGACCUCGGGUCAGGCCCGGGAACCCCGAGAGGAGAGCCCAGCCCCUGGUGGAGGCGGCUUGGCGGAGAUUCGGAGCCGUCAGCAGCUCAGCCAGACGUCCAGGAUCCCACCCCUUGCAAAAGACCAGGCCGUGGAAGCCAUGUUCCCACCAGCCAGGGGGAAGGUGAGCUGUGCCUCCCCCUCUGCUUCAUCAGCAUAGUCACUGCCACCAGCAGCUCCUUCCUCAGACUGAGCCCUCUUGAUCAAUGUGGGGAGUUUUCCUUCUUAGACAGUGCAAUGUAGAGAGCUUAGCCUCUGGAGUCACAUGGGCUUCCUUCAGUUACAUAAACACUCUGGCUCCAGUUUUCUUUUCUGUAAAAUGGGUCAGUGAGAGUGCCUAUCACAGCGAGUUGUGAAGAUUCAAUGAAAAACACCCUGUGAAGUCCUUUGUGCAGUAUCUGGUUACUCGUUUAGCACUGUGUUAAGUUGUUGCUCUUAUUACCGUAGUAGUUGCCCAUUGUUUCUGUCUGUGAGCAUUAUUGUGCACCUACUGCUGUACACUCCAGGUGCUGUUUUCUGUGCUGGGAGAUCAACUCUUACCUGUAGGAGAUUACAACCUGAUUAGAGAGAUAGUUGUGUAAGGAACUUCUCAUAAUAAAUUCUGAACUGUUCCUAUGAACGGGUAUAAUGGAAGGUCAGUUAUUGAAUUUGUAGCAUUAUGGAGGGUGAUUAGAAGAGACUGAGUUGUUUUGUCUUUUUUUUUUUUUGACGGAGUCUCACUCUGUUGCCAGGCUGGAGUGUAGUGGCGCGAUCUCAGCUCACUGCAUCCUCUGCCUCCCGGGUUCAAGUGAUUAUCCUGCCUCAGCCUCCCAAGUAGCUGGGACUACAGGCGAGUGCCACCACGCCCAGCUAAUUUUUGUACUUUUAGUAGAGACGGGGUUUCACCAUGUUGGCCAGAAUGGUCUCCAUCUCUUGACCUCGUGAUCCACCCACCUCAGCCUCCCAGAGUACUGGCAUUACAGGCGUGAGCCACUGUGCCCAGCCUGUGUUUUGUCUUUUUUUAGACGGAGUCUCACACUGUUGCCCAGGCUGGAAUGCAGUGGCAUGAUCAUGGCUCAUGGCAGCCUUGACCUUCCCAGGCUCAGGUGAUCCUCCCACCUCAGCCUCCCAAGUAGUUGGGACCACAGGUACAUGCCACCACGCCUGGUUACUUUUGUAUUUUUUGUAGAGACAGGGUUACACCAUGUUGCCCAGGUUGUUCUUGAACUCUUGGCUUGAGCCAUCCACCAGCCUCAGCCUCCCAAAGUGCUGGGAAUCCAGGUGUGAGCCACCGCGCCCAGCCUAGAAGAGACUGAGUUUGAAAGAAAGGAGAGGACCAGUGGCUCAUGCCUGGAAUCCCAGCACUUUGGGAGGCUGAGGGGGGUGGAUUGCCUGAGGUCAGGAGUUUGAGACCAGCCUGGCCAACAUAUAGUGAAACUCCAUCUCUACUAAAAAUACAAAAAUUAGCUGGGUAUAGUGGCGCAUGCCUAUAAUCCCAUCUACUUGGGAAGCUGAGGCAGGAGAAUUGCUUGAACCGAGGAGGUGGAGGUUGCAGUGAGCCGAGAUCGCGCCAUUGCACUCUAGCCUGGGCAACAAGAGCGAAACUGUCUCAAAAAACAAAAACGAAAACAAAAACCCAAACAAACAAAAAAUGGAACUUUUAAGCAACAUUUGGUGCCCAUCUGUCAAUGUACAAGUCCUAGCUGUUGAUGGGUUCUUGGAAACUGCAACUUUAAGGGAAACUAUGUAUAUCAAAACCGUUUUUUUUCCAUCAGUGUUACAGUGAAACAAAGUUAUUCAAGGACCUGCUGCUGUACAUACUUUUGCUAAAAAUCAGUUUCCAAGAACCUAUUGUGGAUGUUAGGAGAGGAGUUACCAUGCCACAAUGACUCUGGGAGAUGAAGCCAUUUUAUUCCCAUGCUUGUUAACCUUGUGCAGGUGCGGGAAUGCAGAUGGCUGAGUAGGUCAGAUUGAGGACAUGGCAGCGCAGCUCUGGUAAAAGAGUGACACUCUGGAUAAUGGUGAGAAAGGGCCUGCAACCGUAGCAGUGGAACUCAGGUUUGAUAGGCAGGAAAGAAAGUCCGUAUAAUUUGGGAGGUUCUGGUGCCUGCCUGCAGAGGGGAGCUACGUGAAGCUUCUCAGGAUGGUCUCAGGAUGGGGGUGGGCAUUUCCUGUUACUGACCACUUAUAGGACAGCGAACGUUUGCCCUUUCCCUGCACACAUCCCCUCUGAACCCAUGCAGUGUCUUGUGAGAGCAAGGAGUGUGUAGACAGCCGCUGGGCCCCUUUGCCCAGAGGGCUGCAGUGGUGUGGGAGGGAGAGUGUGGCAGCUUCAGUGCUCAGCCCACUGGAGGGGGCAGUCACUUGCAGAUGUAAUGUCCCCUGUGCUCACUGUGCUGUGUCCACUGUUGCCCACUCUGGAUAUGCUCCCCAGGCGUCUGCGCCUUGGUCUGUACCUUUUAUAUUCUCCAGCAACGGGCUCCCCUGGUCUCUGGCAUCUGCUUGGCUUGUGGCAAUGGGAUGAAGAGGGUUGGAGGACAGGGGACAGGGCGCCGGAGGCCUGGGGAAAACUGAGGUUGGGUUUCUCUUCCCACGGCUCCCUCCCCACUGGGCUGUGGGAUGGGUGUGGCUGCAUCCUGUUCAGCCGCAGCUGGUCUUGCUCCCCUUCCAGCAGCCUUCUGGGCUCCAGCAGCCCUCCCCACCUUACCCCUUCAGACCUAGCAGGCCCUGGUUCCCCAGGGUGGCCAGGACCUGCGAGCUUCCACAUUUCUUGUUCAUGUUCAUUGAGACUAUUCAUCCCUUUGUAAAUAGUCUGCACAUUAACCAACCCCCCAGUGACCUCAUCUCUUUCCUAAGGAACCUGGGGCAGAAGCAAUAGGUUAUUUUUAUAGAGCAGCGGUCAGCAAACUGCCCUGGACCGCUUGGUAAAGUUUCCCUGAAACACAGCUGUGCCCAUUCGCUUACUUGUCCACGGCUGCUUUUGUGCUCCAACACAAAGGCUGUUCCUCAGAUUGUUGAUUUGCUGUUCCUCUAAUCAACAGCAGAUUUGAGGAACUGGAACAGAGACCAGAGGGCCUGAAAAGCCUAAAAUAUUUACCAUCUGGCCCUUUAGAGAUUAAUUGUGUCGACCCCGUGGUAUGGAAGCCAGCACAUGUCUGGCCUGAGGGCCAUCAGGCCUGAAAGGAGCCCUGAAUAUAUUCCUUAUGAAUUGGGUGCCCUUGGCCCACACUCUACCUCCCAAACCUUGGUUUCCUCAGCUGUGGAAUAAUCAUUGAGCGUAAGUUAUUUUAAGAAUUGCAGUUACCUUUAUCAGCUACUUUUCCAGGAGCUGCUCUCGUUUGAGGAUGUGGCGAUGUACUUCACCAGAGAGGAGUGGGGCCACCUCAACUGGGGUCAGAAGGACCUCUACCGAGAUGUGAUGUUGGAGAACUACAGGAACAUGGUCUUGCUGGGUAGGACACGGCUUGAAGAUUGGGCUUUGUCUGUGUUCUGAGUGUCUGUGCAAGCCCUUAGUCCCUUAUCUGCAAUUCCAGAAUCAGAAAAAGCGGUGAAAACCGAAAGGUUUUUUUAUAACUCGUGUGGCUACAAGCCCUGACCAGACAUCACCACAGUGAAACCUGACUUCAUCCUAUAGGAAACCAUUUAUUGUCUUUAUUUUUCCAACUUGGUGUGCAUAUCUGUAUACCCAACUUCAGAAAUAACAGUGUGAGCCACUGCACCCAGCUGAGAGUGCUUCUUUACUAUAUCACUGCCUUCUUUUAUGGAUUUUACUAGUUCUAAAAAUAAUUUUCAUUACAGAAAUUUUGGAAAAUACAUCAGUAAAUAGAGUAGAUAAUAAAAAUCACCUGCAGGCCUACUUUCCAGAAGUAACUCUUGUUAUUAACAUUUUGGUUUACUUUUUCCCAGUCCGUCUAUGUGUCUAUUACAGGGAAAGAAUCCCUUAUCCAAAAUGCUGGGGACCAAAAGUGUUUUGGAUUUCGGAUUUUUCUUUUUUGGAUUUUGGAAUACUCAUAAAUAUAUAAUAAGAUAAUUUGAGGAUCUGACAAGAAAUUCACUUAUGUUUCAUAUACACCUUAGACAUGUAGCUUCUUCAAGCUACGCUUGAUUUAAUUGUUCCCUUUUGAUAUUCAGUUUAUUUCCAGUUUGAUGCUGCAAUACCACUGUGCUGAACGUCUCUGGCACAUUCAUCUUGGUUGCAAUUGUACUUUAGGCUAUAUUUCUAAGAGCGAAAUGACCACAGCCAAAGGUAUGAACAUUGUUCAGGCUUUCAAUAAAGACUGCCAGAUAUUUACAAAGAUUGUGCCAAUCUCUGUUUUUCCCUGGGGAAGGCUGAAUUAACUGUGUGUUGUGCACCUGCGUUUUGACUGCCACUGGUCACGUGAGGUCAGGUGUGGAACUCUCCACUUUUAUCAGGUUAGUGCUCAGAAAGUUUCGGAUUUGGGAGCAUUUUGGAUUAGGGAUGUUCAAACUGUAUUAAUUACUUAUACACACACACACAUAACAUACACACUACAUAGUUUUUUAAAACAAAAUUUGGGGUCAGGCAUGGUGGCUCAUGCCUGUAAUCCCAGCACUUUGGGAGGGAGGUCAAGGUGGGCGGAUCACCUGAGGUCGGGAGUUCGAGACCAGCCUGAGCAACAUGGAGAAACCCUGUCUCUACUAAAAAUUCAAAAUUAGUCAGGCGUGGUGGCACAUGCCUGUAAUCUCAGCUAUUCCGGAGGCUGAGGCAGGAGAGAACACUUGAACCCGGGAGGCGGAGGUUGUGGUGAGCCAAGAUUGUGCCAUUGCCCUCCAGCCUGGGCAACAAGAGCAAAACUCUGUCUCAAAAAUAAAAAAAAUUUGGAUCAUGCUAUAUAUGAGUUUUGUAUUCUGCUUUAAAAUACAUAGGCAGUGUUUUCCUAUUUUAAUAAAUAGUUGGGCUGGGCACGGUGGCUCACGCCUGUAAUCCCAGCACUUUGGGAGGCCGAGACAGGUGGAUCACCUGAGGUCAGGAGUUCGAGACCAGUUGGCCAACAUGGUGAAACCUCGUCUCUAUUAAAAAUGUAAAAAUUAGCUGGGCGUGGUGGCCACAUGCCUGUAAUUCCAGCUACUUGGGAGGCCGAGGCAAGAGAAUCACUUGAACCCGGGAGGCGGAGGUUGCAGUGAGCAGAGAUGGUGCCAGUGUACUCCAGCCUGGAUGACAGGAGUGAAACUCCGUCUCAAAAAUAAAUAAAUAAAUAAAAAUAAAAAUACAAAAAUUAGCCGGGUGGGGGCGACAGAGCAGAGACUCCAUCUCAAAAUAAAUAAAUAAAUAAAUUUAUAAAUAAAUAAAUAGUUGGCUAAGUACAGUGGCUCAAGCCUAUAAUCCCAGCACUUUGGGAGGCCAAGGCGGGUGGAUCACCUGAGGUCAGGAGUUCGAGACCAGCCUGGCCAACAUGGUGAAACCCCAUCUCUAAUAAAAAUACAAAACUUAGCAAAGCGUGGGGGCGCUGUGCCUGUAGUUCCAGCUACUUGGGAGGCUGAGGCAGAAGAAUUACUUGAUCCUGGGAGGCAGAGGUUGCAGUGCGCCAAGACUGUCACUCCAGCCUGGGUGACAGAGCAAGACUCUGUCUCAAAAAUAAAAAAAAUAAACAAUUGAAUACAAGGAUUUUUAAUAUCUGCCUAAUACUUAUGCCUUCAUCGCAUUAAUGUGCUACGCUUGAUUUAAUUGUUCCCUUUUGAUAUUCAGUUUAUUUCCAGUUUGAUGCUGCAAUACCACUGUGCUGAACGUCUCUGGCACAUUCAUCUUGGUUGCAAUUGUACUUUAGGCUAUAUUUCUAAGAGUGAAAUGACCACAGCCAAAGGUAUGAACAUUGUUCAGGCUUUCAAUAAAGACUGCCAGAUAUUUACAAAGAUUGUGCCAAUCUCUAUUCUCACCACCGCUUUUGAUUAUUGUCCUUAUCUCUGCUUGCCACUGAGCCCCGGGCCAUGUCUCUGUAACUCACUAACGGCCACAUCCCAUUUACUUCCCCAUGAGUAGGAUUUCAGUUUCCCAAACCUGAGAUGAUCUGUCAGCUGGAGAACUGGGACGAGCAGUGGAUCCUGGAUCUACCGAGAACUGGGAAUAGGAAGGCUUCCGGUAGUGCUUGCCCAGGUGGGUGAGGAAGAGACCCAGGCGAGUGGAAUCAGGAAGAGGAAGGGAAGGCAUGUUAGUGAAGCCCCUUCUGUGUGCCAGACGCUGAGCCAGGUGCUGGGCAUAUAUUAUCCCACUUCUUCAUCCCUACUGCCCUGUGAAGUGGGAGGAAGAUCGGCGUCCCCAUUUCCCAGAUGAAGAAACUAAGAUUAAGAAAUCUUGGCUGGACGCGGUGGCGCAUUCCUGUAAUCCUACUUUGGGAGGCCAAGUUGGGCGGAUCACCUGAGGCCAGGACUAGACCAGCCUGGCCAACAUGGUGAAACCCCGUCUCUACUGAAAAUAUAAAAAUUAGCCCCGCGUAGUGGCGUGUGCCUGUAAUCCCAGCUACCUGGGAGGCUGAGGCAGGAGAAUCACCGGAACCUGGGAGGCAGAGGCUGCAGUGAGCCGAGAUCGCGUCACUGCACUCCAGCCUGGGUGACAGAGCAAGACUGUCUCAAUUAAAAAAUAUAUAUAUAUAUCACACAGGCCUGGUAUGGGGGCUCACGCCGGUAAUCCCAGCACUUUGGGAGGCAGAGGCAGGAGGAUCACUUGAGCCCAGGCGUUCAGGAUCACCCUGGGUGAUAUGGUGAAACCCCAUCUCUACAAAAAAUACAAAUUUAAGCCGGGUGUGGUGGCGCAUGCCUGUAGUCCCAGCUACUCAGGAGGCUGAGGUGUGAGGACUGCUUGAGCCUGGGAGGCAGAGGUUGCAGUGAGCUGAGAUUACAUGACUGUACUCCAGCCUGGGUGACAGAGCAAGACUGUCUGAAAAAAGAACUCUCACAGUUGGGAGGUGGACACUGGGGUUUGACUUCAAGUCUAGAAUGCUUAUCCUCUCUCUCCUGCAGGAAAAAGUGCUGCUCUGACGCAGAUGCUCUAGUGUUUUCUAAGUGACAGCUCUUAGGGCACCCUGGAUGCCCCUUGAUUCCACCCUCAUUACUUGUCCUCUCUCGGUGCUGCCUCUUGUUCCCUUGCUUUGUUUUGUUUUCAUAUUACUCCCGUAUUUCCUGACAUAUCUGCAUUUUUCUACUUACUGUGUCCCGAUGCAGCUGCUCCUGUUUUUCACAUCCAAGGUUUCUCCUCCAUGGCACUACUGACGUUUUGGGCUGACGAAUUCUUUGGGGACAGGAUGGGGCAUGUCCUGUGCAUUUUAGGAUGUUGAGUAGCAGCCCUGGCCUGCAUCCACUAGAUGCCAGUUGAACCUCCCCAGGUUCUGAAGCCAGACACAAGAUGAAAAAGCUAACUCCAAAACAGAAAUUUUCUGAAGAUUUAGAGUCAUAUAAGAUAUCAGUGGUAAUGCAGGAAUCAGCUGAGAAACUUUCAGAAAAGUUACAUAAGUGUAAAGAAUUUGUGGACAGUUGCAGGCUUACUUUCCCUACUAGUGGUGAUGAAUACAGCAGGGGCUUCCUUCAAAACCUUAACCUUAUUCAAGAUCAGAAUGCGCAAACAAGGUGGAAGCAGGGCAGAUAUGAUGAGGAUGGCAAACCCUUCAAUCAAAGAUCUUUGCUUUUGGGGCAUGAGCGAAUUCUCACAAGAGCAAAGUCUUAUGAAUGCAGUGAAUGUGGAAAAGUCAUUAGGCGUAAGGCAUGGUUUGAUCAACAUCAAAGAAUUCACUUUUUAGAGAAUCCUUUUGAGUGUAAGGUCUGUGGGCAAGCCUUCAGACAGCGGUCAGCUCUUACGGUCCAUAAACAGUGUCACCUGCAAAACAAGCCAUACAGAUGUCAUGACUGUGGAAAGUGUUUUCGGCAGCUCGCGUAUCUUGUUGAACAUAAGAGGAUUCACACCAAAGAAAAACCUUAUAAAUGUAGCAAAUGUGAAAAAACGUUUAGUCAGAAUUCAACCCUUAUUCGACAUCAGGUGAUCCAUAGUGGAGAAAAACGCCAUAAAUGCCUUGAGUGUGGAAAAGCCUUUGGCCGGCAUUCAACCCUUCUAUGUCAUCAACAGAUUCACAGUAAACCGAACACCCAUAAAUGCAGUGAAUGUGGACAGUCCUUUGGUAGGAAUGUGGAUCUCAUUCAGCAUCAAAGAAUCCAUACAAAGGAGGAAUUCUUUCAAUGUGGAGAAUGUGGGAAAACGUUUAGUUUUAAGAGGAAUCUUUUUCGACAUCAGGUCAUUCACACUGGAAGCCAACCCUACCAAUGUGUCAUAUGUGGAAAAUCUUUCAAGUGGCACACAAGCUUUAUUAAGCACCAGGGCACUCACAAAGGACAGAUAUCCACAUGAUGUUAAUUGGAAAGCAGUCAUUGGAGAACUAGAACUUAUAAACCUCUACUUCAAGUGUGUAUCACGUAAUUGUUUCCAUGAAAAGCAAUAAAUGUAACAAAGGGUUUUUCUAUGGGA